CAAAAAAAGAAAAAGUGAUAUUAUGCAGCUAUGUUAAAUUUUUCUUUCCUGUCAUUGUAUUGGUUCACUAGUUACAACAAGCAUAUAUUAUUAAUACUUUUGCAAUUAAAAAGUCCAAUUAAGGCAAUUAAAAGGCAAAGAAAAACCUGUCUGCCCAAGUGGAAUGGAAAUUCUAUGAGGCAAGGAUCGUGUGCAUUUUGCUCACUGCUGUCUCUCAGAAACGGCUAACGCCUCUCUCCAUAUGGCGACUGCACAGGAGAUGCUUGUUGGUGAAUGGAUGAACAUAGCCAUGGCUGUGAUGCAGGUGAAGUGCUGUUUGGGGAGCAAAGGGAGGUCAGCUGAGGUUCUUGGUCAUCAAGUGCCGUGGCUUCUGCUGGUUUCACCAGCUCACCCACUUCUCCUCUUCUCUGAUGUUGCUCUGGGGAACUACCCAGUCCCCAGUGCACGUUCUUGUUGGGAGAAUUAGUCAAGGUGUCUGCCCUCAGGGGCCAAAGAGUGGGCCCCUGAGCUAAGCCAGGCCAGUUGGGGCCUCUUGCUGAGAAUCUGGAUUGAAAAGAACCCUGCAUAGAUGGACUGUGGGAGAGCCGACUCAUGCUGGAGGCAGCGCCUGACAACAACAGCCACCAACUCCUGGUGCGUGCCACCCAGGUCCCUGCAGCUGCUUCCUGUUCUUUCCCGGAGAGUUCUCCAGUUUCCUUUUGAGUCUAUGAGACCCUCCUCUCAUCACCAUCCUUCCAAUCAAUCUUAACCUCCCCGCAACCCCAUAAUCAAAUGGGUUUCUGUUGCUUGUAACCCAACAGCCCUGAUAAUGUUCAGAGAUAACUGGAAAGUCCUUGCACUCUUCCUCUUUCAUGACCCUGUAAGCUAGGGUGACCAUCAGUCUACAGAGCUCCAGGGCAGCCCUGGCCUACAGCCAUUGUCCAGGCCUAAUUAUUAAUAUCAUCCCUUUAGUCUCCUCGUCUGAAUGAUCAAUUAUGUGAUCAGCCUACUUAUAGCUAUCUUUUGGUCUUCCUCACUUUGGCAAAGGAUUAUCUUCUGUUUUGCUUUAUCUGAGCCACUUUCCCAGAACAAUAGCAGAGAUCUCUCUAUUCACCUGCUUACAAAAAAAACAAAAAACAAAACCAAACAAAAAACCCCAGCAACAACAAGAUAUUCUCUUGAUUGAUAAAUAACCCACAUUCGAGGCUUAUUCAUUAUUGUUCCUGUGGCAAAGUAUAGAUUCUUUAGGCCAAUCUCCUCCAUAAUAUUUUGAAAAGUAUGGAAAAUGUCACCUUUACCUCUUUUGUCUUCUAGGUUGCUUGUCUUUUCUCUCCUGCGUAAUUUCCACUUUCAUUCAUGAUAAUGUCGAACACGCUCAAUCACCUAAGAAGACCAAAGAAAAAUCCCCUGCAAAGAGGAUCAUCAUUUCCUUGAAGAUCAAUGACCCACUGGUCACUAAAGUCGCCUUCGCCACGGCCCUGAAGAACCUCUACAUGAGUGAGGUGGAGAUUAACUUGGAAGACCUACUGGGAGUGCUGGCUUCCGCCCACAUCCUCCAGUUCAGUGGCCUGUUUCAAAGGUGCGUGGAUGUGAUGAUAGCCAGACUCAAGCCAAGCACCAUCAAGAAAUUCUACGAGGCCGGCUGCAAGUACAAGGAAGAGCAGCUCACCACCGGCUGCGAGAAGUGGCUGGAAAUGAACUUGGUUCCUCUAGGGGGGACGCAGAUCCACCUCCACAAAAUCCCACAGGACCUGCUCCACAAAGUGCUGAAGUCCCCCAGGUUAUUUACCUUUAGUGAAUUCCAUCUUCUGAAAACAAUGCUUUUGUGGGUCUUCUUGCAACUGAACUACAAGAUUCAGGCAAUUCCGACUUAUGAAACCGUGAUGACAUUUUUUAAGAGCUUUCCUGAGAACUGUUGCUUUCUGGACCGGGACAUAGGACGGAGCUUGAGGCCGCUCUUCCUCUGCUUGCGUCUGCACGGCAUCACCAAAGGCAAGGAUCUGGAGGUGCUGCGGCACCUUAACUUCUUCCCAGAGUCAUGGCUCGACCAGGUUACAGUCAACCAUUACCACGCACUGGAGAAUGGGGGCGACAUGGUCCACCUGAAAGAUCUUAACACCCAGGCUGUGAGAUUUGGGCUGCUCUUUAACCAGGAGAAUACAACUUAUUCGAAAACGAUUGCUCUAUAUGGAUUCUUCUUUAAGAUAAAGGGACUCAAACAUGAUACUACCUCUUAUAGUUUUUACAUGCAGAGAAUAAAGCACACAGACCUGGAAUCUCCCUCUGCGGUCUACGAGCACAACCACGUCAGCCUGCGAGCGGCACGCCUGGUGAAGUAUGAGAUCAGAGCAGAGGCCCUGGUUGACGGCAAGUGGCAGGAGUUCAGGACAAACCAGAUCAAGCAGAAGUUUGGGUUGACCACGUCAUCCUGCAAAAGCCAUACCUUGAAAAUCCAAACUGUGGGCAUCCCAAUCUAUGUAAGUUUUGCAUUCAUCUUCCCAGCAUCUUGACAGUUUCCAGAAGAAUCUAUGGGAUUUUCCCCCCACUGGUCUGCAUAAAAGAAAAUAAAAUGACAUAAAAGGGA